CUCUCCGCAGCUUCCGGCCAAGUUGGACUGCAGCUCGCGGUUUCCUGGCUUCUAGGGGUAUUGCAGGCACCAAUGGAACAGGUUGGGGAGGAGAGUUUGGGACCAAGAACACCCAUGAACCCUUAGAAGCCACCAUAGAGAUCCCUACAUCCCACCCCAAGAGCUGCAGAGUGUCCUGCUGAGAUCGCUGUGUGUCAGCAUCUGCAGAAACUACCUUCUCCUCCAACCUGACUGUCCUGACCUGAAGGACAGCCUGCCCAAGGACUUCUAGUACACCAGGCUCUCCACUGGGCCCUUGAACUGGUGAUGGUUGAUGGGACUCCCCUAGUCUGCUCCCAAGCUAGAAGCUGCAGAAUGUGAUGACCUGGGGUCCCUGCUCGGAGCCUGGCCUCCCGGGAGUCUACACACCUGUGAAUCCCUUCAUUUCCUGGAUCCAAGAUAAUGUCUCCAACGUCUCCUUUGACACCUCUGCCAACAGAUGCUGUUGGGGCUGGCCCAGGACAAGACAGAGGCAGUGAGGGUUGUUAGCCUCUGGAGUCCUGGGUUUGAAUCCUGACUUAGCUACUUACCUGCCUUUGCCAUCUGAAUCUGUUUCCUCCUCUGUAAAAUGGAGAUGUCUUCAAUUAUUCAUUUAUCAACAAGUUAGUAGUUACCAAGUGCUUACUCUGUGACAGGCCACUAAGAUACAAGACUGUAUCUUGACAGAUUCGUGGAUUUUGGCUAGCAACUCCCCUGAGCGCUGGCUGAUUGGGGUGCCAGGCGCCGCCCGCUGCGGGCCUCAGUUUCCCCAGCUUCGAACUAAAGAGCGAUGGCUUGGAUGUAAGGAUUCUUGAGGUCCCUCCCAAGUUUGUUUAAUAAACUUUUUCGAGGGCAAGCGUCUCCAAGCCACAGGGGCGCAUCCUUUUCACCUGCUUGGACGCUGCUUGGCCCCAGCUGGGGAGGCUCCUCCGAGCACCCGGCAUUCCAGAGUUAGCCCCGACAGCUGUGGUCACGUCGCCCGUGCUCUGCAGCGCCUCCCUCCGCGUCCUCGCGGUGGGGCCACAGCGACAUCUAGUGGCUGAAUGUAUUUUAAACACUCGGCUUGCUGAGGGCGUGAGUCGGAGCGCUGCUCCCCAGGACUCAGCUCUCAUUCGCCUCUGCGCUUCGGCGGGGACGGGGAGCCGGGCCGAGUCAGAGUGAACACACACUCCCUGCGCGUGCAACUGAGUCGAGCGGUAGGGCUGGCUUUACCCGACAGGUCAACGCUCCCGCCCCAGCUCUCGGUCAUACCUGCCCUAAGGAGGGGUGGAGCCUCGGCGUGGAUCCCCGCCCCUUGUGCCCCGCCCCCUUAUAACGGCGCCCGUUCACUGCGCCUGCGCAUGCCACACGCGCACUCGCGUGGCCUUCGCGAAGGUGUCGCUGCCAAGAAACGUGUCCUGCGCGCUACGCCGUCUGUUUCUAGGGCAACGCCGGCGUCUCUUAGCAACCGCGCGCGGCCUAGGUGGGUCCCCCCGGCACCCCCAGACCUGCCAUGGCGACCGCGAGUCCUAGCGUCUUUCUACUCAUGGUCAACGGGCAGGUGGAGAGCGCCCAGUUUCCAGAGUAUGAUGACCUCUACUGCAAGUACUGCUUUGUGUACGGCCAGGACUGGGCCCCCACAGCGGGUCUGGAGGAGGGGAUCUCACAGAUCACAUCCAAGAGCCAAGAUGUGCGGCAAGCACUGGUGUGGAACUUCCCCAUUGAUGUCACCUUUAAAAGCACCAACCCCUACGGCUGGCCACAGAUCGUGCUCAGCGUGUAUGGACCAGAUGUGUUCGGGAACGAUGUGGUUCGAGGCUAUGGGGCCGUGCACGUGCCCUUCUCACCUGGCCGGCACAAAAGGACCAUCCCCAUGUUUGUCCCAGAAUCUACGUCUAAACUGCAGAAGUUUACAAGCUGGUUCAUGGGGCGGCGGCCCGAGUACACAGACCCCAAGGUGGUGGCUCAGGGUGAAGGCCGGGAAGAUGAGAACGCUGAGGCUGAGAUUCCCAGAUCAACCUGGGUCUCUCUCUGCCCCAGCCCAGCCUGGCUGAUGCUGCCCUUCUGUCCCCAGUGACCCGUGUCCGUUCUCAGGGCUUUGUCACCCUCCUCUUCAACGUGGUGACCAAGGACAUGAGGAAACUGGGCUAUGACACUGGGCCUUCUGAUACACAGGGUGUGUUGGGGCCCAGCCCACCCCAGAGCUUCCCCCAGUGAAGGCUCCACAGGCUGCACAGUCUCUGAUAAUGAAGGGCUGCCUUCCCGAAGUCAGCCGCUGCCCAUCGGCCUGAGGGGCAGCCUGGUGGCCAGAGCUGGGGGCACACAGAAUAGUUUUGUAUAAUAAAGUCUCAUUUUCAGAGAGCCUAGGCCUGGGGCUGCCUUCUCUCCUGUUUAGCCCCUCCCCCACAGGAGCUGGGGGCUCUUGGGCCUUUCCUGGCCCCACCUCCAGGGCUCUCCCUGUCCCUACCCCUUGUGCCGUGGAAGCUGCCAGGAGACCAGACCGUGCAGCAGGAUGGCAUGUGGGAUGGGAGCUUUGACAUAACCAGGUUCUGCCACUCAAAGCUGUGUGGCCUUUUCUAUACCGCAACACAUUGUUCCUUGAACUAACUGGGCAUGGCACCCUCCUUAGAGGCUUGGGGUUAAGUAGAAUCACCCGUUCAGCCAUGCUUCUGGCCACCAGCCUCCCUUGGCAAGGACAGAACCCUGUUAUUGGGAGCUGGAAUGGUGAGGUACCCCGGGGGAUGGCAGACCCUCAGCCUGCCCACUCCCCUCUCUGCCCCCCUACCCACAGUCCAAGGAUGGGGGCUGGAAACCUCUCAGAGGUGGGAGGCCGCUGGCUGGGGUCCAGCUUUCUGGCAGCCCCUUGGCAGGAGAGGAAGGUGAGCCCCCUGGCUCAACACCCUGACCUCUGAGGUUGUCCAGGCCCUUCUGGAAGCAGAGCCCCUUCAGCAUUACUUUGGGAGGCCCUGACCCUGGGCCUCCCCACCUUCACAAGAACCCCUCGCACCUCACGAGGCAGCCCCAGGCCCUCUCUGCCCUGCCACUGAGCUUUCGGCAGACAUGGUGCCCCAGCCUAGAUACUGCCCUCAGCGGGAUCCAAGAGAAACCACAGGCUCCUGGCAAACCCCCACCUCCCAGCCUCGCCCAUGUUGCCCUGGACUGUCGUCAUGGCACUUGCCCUGAGACCAUCUGGGCCGACCCUCUUCUGCCUUUUAUCUCACGAGCACUCCCGUGCCCUCCCCCCAACUCACUGUGCGUUCUGAAACUCAUCGUCUGUUGUCAGCAAAAUUCCUGUGAUUCCAUCUUCUCGGAAUAGGAAGUUCCCUCUGCCUUCUGGCCUUACUGAAGCCCACUCAGUACCCUGCAGCCCUCUUAAGUGGAAUCUUUUUCCUCCCACUCCCCAUGUGCGGUGAGCCUAGAGCAGGGGUGUGUCCUUGCCUCUUCCUCAACCUCCUCACUUGGAACAGUCUGUCUUCACCUCUACCCCUCACAGCCAGGCAGGCAUAUCUCUUGUUACUGGUGAAGGCACUGCCUCCAAAGUCUGGAUUGAGGCAUCCCUCCCUCAGGCCAGGCCCUCCCUCAUGUGGCGCUUCCCUGUGCUCUUCAAACCACCAGGCCCUCCAAGCUCCUGGCCCAGCCCCUUUUCGCCAACCAUCAGCCCCUCUUUCCUUGCUUUCCUCCCAGCCCAGUUUAGAACUCUUGGUCAUCUGCAUGCACUUCCCAUAGUGCCCUCCAUCCUUCGUUUAUGCUCACCUGGCAAGGUCUCCACCCUGGUGACAGCCAGCUGUUCCUUCGCCUGCCCUGCACCUGCCUGAGCCCCCAGAGCCACAACGGCUCGCGUUCCAUCCAUGGCCCAGGUCUGUGUUUCCCUAGACAACUCCCUCAUGCAUUCUCUGAGGAAACUUAACAGCCUUUGUCUCUUCAGGCCUCCAGCACCCUCCCUGCCAGCUUAGCUAAGGCGCUCCCUUCUGUUCCCACAACCACCCCACAUUAGCUGCCUUCCUUACCCUACCUGAGGACAUGCCUCAGGUGUGUGGGAGAUACAGUGCUCUCAAGGGUCUUUCUUCUCCCCUUCUCCCUCCAUCGUGAGUUUUCCUACACGGGCUCCUUCACGCCAGCCUCCACAUGUGCCCCACGUGUCAUGGGACGACACAGAGCAAAAGCCCAGCACCCUCAGCUGCUCCUGUCCUCUGCCCCAUUUUAUCACAGCUAUCACAGCUCCCCGGAAAGCUGUCUUCUCUGUCCAUGGCCUCACCUCACCCAGGGCACUGGCCUUGGUCCACAUCAAGGGGACCUGAAGCUUCCCUGAAGCCUCUAGCCUGUGGUGUGCACGUACAAGCCUCAGGCCCCAUUUGUCCAGCCUGUCAGCAGCUGGGAAAUACUAAGUCACCCUCUUCUGGUUAUGUUUAAUUUUCCAAUUUUUCUCAACAUUACUGAAAUGUCUAAAUGUGGAAAAGUUGACAUCAUUUUACAGUGAACACCACAUACCCACCACCUAGAUUUUACCAUUACCAAUUUCCUGUUCCGUACUUGUAUAUUCACAUAUAUCCAACUAUUCAUCCCUGCUUCAAUCCAUCCUAUUUUUAUUGCAUUUCAAAAUAAACUGUGAAAUCAGGACUCCACCUUCUGUAUAUUUCAGCACACUUACCAUUAACCAGAAUCCAGUGUCUGGCUUUAGUGUGUUCUUUUGAGGGGACAUUUACGUACAACAAAAUGCGUAACUCUUUUUUUUUUUUUUUUUUUUUUUGAGACAGGGUCUUACUCUGUCGCCCAGGCUGGAAUGCAGUGGCACGGUCCUGGCUGACUGCAACCUCUGCCUCCCGGGUUCAAGUGAUUCUCCUGCCUCAGCCUCCCGAGUAGCUUAAAAUUACAGGCACCUGCCACUGAAGCUGGCUAAUUUUUGUAUUUUUAGUAGAGACAGGGUUUCAGGGUUUCACCAUGUUGGCCAGGCUGGUCUUGCACUCCGGACCGCAGGUGAUCCGCCUGCACCAGCUUCCCAAAGUGUUGGGAUUACAGGCAUGAGCCACUGCGCCUGGCCAAGAAUACUUUAAGAAUGCACAACCAGGCCGGACAUGGUGCUGACGCCUGUAAUCCCAGCACUUUGGGAGGCUGAUGCAGGCGGAUCACCUGAGGUCAGGACUGUUAAGACCAGCCUGGCCAACAUGGUGAAACCCCGUCUCUACUAAAAAUACAAAAAGUUAGCCAGGCAUGGUGGCGGGCGCCUGUAAUCCCAGCUACUCGGGAGGCUGAGGCAGGAGAAUCGCUUGAACCCGGGAGGUGGAGGUUGCAGUGAGCCAAGACUGUGCCACUGCACUCCAGCCGGGGCGACAGAGGGAGACUCCAUCUCAAAAAAGAAUGCACAACCCAGCCCCAAAGGCACAGAAAUGUCACUGUCACUUCACAAAGCUCCUUGCAUCCCUGCCCAGUCAAGCCACCUUCAGGGCUGUCUGUCAAAGAUAGCAGUGUUUCAAGAUGAAAGCGGCUUGAGUCCCUGAGUCACUGACUUCUGUGAGAAACUUCCGCGGGAAGCCGCUGAGACCUGGAGAUGUGUUACUGCAGCGUAACCAAGAGCAUCCCACACACCCUUCUUUCUCUCCUGUCCCCUGCACUGAACGGGCACCCCCUGCCACCAGUCCCUAGCCUCCUAGCUCUGAGUCAAGCUUGUCUGCUUAUCCUUGGGUGGACACCAGGAGCCAGGCACUUGCACAGAGAGCAGAGGGCUGCAGGGCAGUCCCAGACCUCCCUCCAGGCUCGUCUCAAGGCCUCUCCAACCCUUCCCAUCAGGGUCUCCCAGCCGCCUCUGCCUCGGCCUUGCCUCUUCCCGUGACCAGAGCACCUCUUCCACCUCUGCUGCCUGGAGAUGCACGUGUCCUCCCGCCGCUGCCCUCGUCUGGUUGGUGGCUCUGAGGCACAGGCCCUCUGUCGGUCAGCUGUUGCACAGCAAGCCACCUAAGAACCAGUGGCUCCAACAGGCCCUUCCUCUCAGGAACACGCAGUUGGCUGGGCAGCUCCACGCACUCCCUCCCUCUGUUGCCUCAGCUGACAGGCAGUGGCUUCCCAGAGCAGCUCUUCUGCAGCAUGGACACAAGAGGAGGCAGAGCACAGGAAGCCUCUGGGGACCCGGCACACUGUCACUUCCACCUCAUCCAAAGCAGCCUCCACCAGUGACAAGGCCGCAUUAAGAGGGCGGACACAGAAGGGUAAAGGGCAGUGGCUAGCACUUCCCCCAGCACACCCGUGCAGGCCACCAGUCUCAGCACCUCACAAAAGGCACGCCUCCCACCCCCUUUCCCUGAGGUUCAGGGGCAACCAAAUGCCCAGCUCACGCGGGCACUAGGACCAGGCUGGUGGCCUCAAUAACUGCAGACCAAGCUCCACAAGAAUCGGCUCCCUCAUCUCCCACCUCUCCAGUGGCACAGGACUGAUGAAGAUGGGGUGGGAGAAGGACACAGCCAGAAACCGCAUCAUGGUACAAAUGAUAAAUUAUAUUUAUACAGUAAAUAAGUAUCAACAGUCAACACAAGUUCAAAACCAGCCACCGGCCUCUGGGACUGAGAAACAGCUGGGUGACUUCCUCCACCACGGUGCCCAUCAGGAGGGAGCACGAUGGCACAGGUGCAACAUGCGUGGCAGUGGCCGGUGGCUUCAUGAUCAGUGCAGUGGGCAACAGGGACAUGCACUCGGGAUGGCCUGUGCCAGAAGAUGGGGCAGGGGGCUGUCUUCUUGGGUCCCGGUGGCCCAGUGGCUGUCAUGUUGGGGCCUCAAAGUCACAUCAUGAAAGACUCGUUACAAAAGAAUCACUGACCCCAAGUAGUCGAGUCUAGUCUACUGACCUGUAAGGCUGGCCCAGGCCCUGCACCGUCUGAAGGAAAGCACCUUUCUGGGCAAGCAUCCUGCCUCCCAUCCCAUUGCACCUCCCCACCCUUCCCCCGGCAGACGAGACCAGCCACCGGCUUACCCAAAUGGCAGCGGGAGCCUAAGACCCAGCCGCAGGCCUGCAGUUCUGGCAGAAGGUGGCUGGUCAGGAACUCUAGACACGGCUCCUGGGACUGGAGAGGGCGGCCUCAGGAACAGCAUGAGUGGGUGCAGUCCCCACUCAGAGCCUGCAUGUCCCAGCAGCCCAGAGACCAUUUAAGAUCUCUCCUGUGCCGGUGCGAAGGGUAAUCUUCUGGAACCAGAGAGGGGCUGGCAGGUGGUCAGCUGCCCUUAGAGCUAGAGGUGAGAAAUUCCCAUGGUGGAAAAAGGGCCAGAAACAUCCACCAGGCAAGCUGCCCAGACACAGGAUUGGGGGAAUGUCCCCUCCCUGGGUAAAAGCAAGUCUUUUCUGGUCUUUAAUGCACGACGUAAUACUUUUACAGUGGUGGGUGAGGUGAGGACAGUAGGAGUUUGGAAGAGGGAGGUAAUAUUAGUGCAUGUUUGUUAAAAAUCCCUCCCAGGUGAAUGACUUUUUUCUUCAUCUCCAAAAUACAAGAGAAUUAUUUUUAGGUCUCCAACUUAAAAAUAAUAUCUGGAGUUAGCAGGUAGGUGGAUCAGGGCCAGCCCUGGUCCCUUAGCCCCCCACCCCUGUCUUAGCCUAGGGACUGUUGCCCAGGGACCCGUGGGCACAGAAGCACCCCCCACCCCACGCCCUCGGGACAACUGCCAUUUCCACAUUAUCCCCAUCUUUAGCCUGAGCGUGGAUUAAGACAGAGGAGAUCACAGACACACAAGGUUAAAGAUGUUUCUUCCAUUUCAGAUUUCCAUUGUAAACAGAAGUCCUGUUAAUCCCUGCAUGCCUUUAAUAAAAAAAAGGAAUUAGUUGAUAAAAAUUGGUGAGUCACAUUCAUACAUUAGAUUUUUUUCUUUAACUUUCAGGAUGUUGGUAUAUUCGUAAGAAAAAUAGCCUCUCAGGAUCUAGCCAAAAAGGCUGAAAGUCAAUCAGUUUAGUAAUUCACCAAAAACAGGAGCUAAAGAAAGGAAAAGGCAACUGGAGGCUAGGAUUUUUUGUUGCUGUUGUUUUUUUUUUAAAUAAACAUCAUCAUCUAUGUGUAAUCAAAUUCCCAUAUUUUCUUCCUAUAAAGAAUUUGCUUUAGUUUUUCAAUAAGGCAUUUUUUUGUCAUCCAAACAUCUCUUCCUUUUAAAAUUUUCUUAGAGUUAAAACCAUAAAUAAGAGGAUUUAAACCACUAAAAUGACACGUGCCAACAUCUUCAUUCAGCCAGACCUGGUAAAUUCUAUCAAAACUAGACAGUUAAAUAAGAACCACGUUAUAAAAAUAUUAGCCAAAAAAAGACUAUUAGAUAAUUCUGCAAACUCAAAUAUGAAACUGUACUAAACAAAAUAUGUGCAAAGGUACACAAGCAUAGAGCCACGUUGGGGGUUAUGCUCAGAUUAGUUUUAAAGCUCGCUCUAGUGGAUUUAAUUCAAGAGUUGUCCACGGUGGUGGUGUUUACUUUGAACUCACACGAGUCAAAGAAAAAUAAAAUAUGCACAACCACUUCCCCAAAA